AGCUGUAGUGCUUCUGGGCAGUAGAGGCGCGGGGUGCGGAGCUAGGGCGGCCGAGAGCCAUGGCGGCGCUAUUGGCGGCGGCGGCAGUGCGAGCCCGGAUCCUGCAGGUUUCUUCCAAGGUGAAAUCCAGUCCCACCUGGUAUUCAGCAUCUUCCUUCUCUUCUUCAGUGCCAACUGUAAAGCUCUUCAUUGGUGGGAAAUUCGUUGAAUCCAAAAGUGACAAAUGGAUCGAUAUCCACAACCCAGCCACCAAUGAGGUCAUUGGUCGGGUCCCUCAGGCCACCAAGGCAGAAAUGGAUGCAGCCAUUGCUUCCUGCAAACGUGCUUUUCCUGCAUGGGCAGACACUUCAGUAUUAAGCCGCCAGCAGGUCUUGCUCCGCUAUCAACAACUUAUUAAAGAAAACUUGAAAGAAAUUGCCAAGUUAAUCACAUUGGAACAAGGGAAGACCCUAGCUGAUGCUGAAGGAGAUGUAUUUCGAGGCCUUCAGAAUCUCAUUUUGCACAAACCCUUAACUUGGAAGGGCAAGUCAGUGUACCCUGCACCCCUUCAUUGGCCUGAACCACUUCCUGUCCUCAGGGCUGAAGAGAACAGGACAAAGCUAACUAGUACACAGUGUGGAGAGCUGAUGGCCUGACUUCUGUGUUCCAGAGGUGGUUGAGCAUGCCUGUAGUGUGACAUCCCUCAUGAUGGGAGAGACCAUGCCAUCCAUCACCAAAGACAUGGACCUUUAUUCCUACCGUCUGCCUCUGGGAGUGUGUGCAGGCAUUGCUCCAUUCAAUUUUCCUGCCAUGAUCCCCCUUUGGAUGUUUCCCAUGGCCAUGGUGUGUGGAAAUACCUUCCUAAUGAAACCAUCUGAGCGAGUCCCUGGAGCAACUAUGCUUCUUGCUAAGUUGCUCCAGGAUUCUGGUGCCCCUGAUGGAACAUUAAACAUCAUCCAUGGACAGCAUGAAGCUGUAAAUUUUAUUUGCGAUCAUCCGGACAUCAAAGCAAUCAGCUUUGUGGGAUCCAACAAGGCAGGAGAGUAUAUCUUCGAGAGAGGAUCAAGACAUGGCAAGAGGGUUCAAGCCAAUAUGGGAGCCAAGAACCAUGGGGUAGUCAUGCCAGAUGCCAAUAAGGAAAAUACCCUGAACCAGCUGGUUGGGGCAGCAUUUGGAGCUGCUGGUCAGCGCUGCAUGGCUCUUUCAACAGCAGUCCUUGUGGGAGAAGCCAAGAAGUGGCUGCCAGAGCUGGUGGAGCAUGCCAAAAACCUGAGAGUCAAUGCAGGAGAUCAGCCUGGAGCUGAUCUUGGCCCUCUGAUCACUCCCCAGGCCAAAGAGCGAGUCUGUAAUCUGAUUGAUAGUGGAACAAAGGAGGGAGCUUCCAUCCUUCUUGAUGGACGAAAAAUUAAAGUGAAAGGCUAUGAAAAUGGCAACUUUGUUGGACCAACCAUCAUCUCGAAUGUCAAGCCAAAUAUGACCUGUUACAAAGAGGAGAUUUUUGGUCCAGUUCUUGUGGUUCUGGAGACAGAAACAUUGGAUGAAGCCAUCCAGAUUGUAAAUAACAACCCAUAUGGAAAUGGAACUGCCAUCUUCACCACCAAUGGAGCCACUGCUCGGAAAUAUGCCCACUUGGUGGAUGUUGGACAGGUGGGAGUGAAUGUCCCCAUUCCAGUGCCUUUGCCAAUGUUCUCAUUCACCGGCUCUCGAUCCUCCUUCAGGGGAGACACCAAUUUCUAUGGCAAACAGGGCAUCCAAUUCUACACUCAGUUAAAGACCAUUACUUCUCAGUGGAAAGAAGAAGAUGCUACUCUUUCCUCACCUGCUGUUGUCAUGCCUACCAUGGGCCGUUAGAAACAAGUUUGUUUAAGACUGACUCCAUCCUGAGUAAUCUCCCUUUAUUUUUGACCAGCUUCAUUUGUCAGCUUUGCUCAGAUCAGAUCGAUGGGAUUGGAAUACAUUGUAACUAAAAUCUUCCUCAGGACUAUUAACCCCCGCAAAGUUUCUAUAGGGAACUGCCUAGUGUAACAAUGAAACCAGAUUUCUCACUUGCUCUUCAUACUUCUAUUUUGAGGUAACUGUUGUAACUAUGAAAUGCUUAUCUGAAAGUAGUGCUUAAACCUGAUUUCUAAAAAUUAUCCCAUUUUCUGAUGAUUUGAAGGGGAGAAAAGCCAGUGUAUGUAAAGAAAAUGUUCCAGCCAGGCGCGGUGGCUCACGCCUGUAAUUCCAUCAUUUUGGGAGGCCACAGUGGGCAGAUUGCUUGAGCCCAGGAGUUGAAGAACGUGGCGAAACCCCGUAUCUAUUAUUUAAAAAAAUUGAAAAAGUAAAAAAAGAAAAGGGAAAAAAAAUUUUUUAAAGAAGAUGUUCCAAUAAUUGCAAGAAGAACUCUUAGAUGGGGAAACAGGACAGAAAUAACUCACCGCUUUUGGUUGAUCCUCAAACAUAGCGCUACCUAAAUGCCACUGGGAGAGACCUCCUGCAAAGUUUUCUUUAGCCCCUCUUUUAUCCCACAAUACACAAGAUAUAAUCCAUUUUUAUAUAUCCCAAAGUUGUGGCAACAGCUUCUUUCUUUUCUGCUCAAUGCCACUUUGUUUCCUAGUAAUUCAUGACCACUAUUAAUUCUAUCAUUGUCACUGCUCCUGCUUAAGAUCACUUCUCAAGGAUACCUCAGUAAGCAAUGGAUAAAUCAACUUUUUGUUAUAUGUGCCAAGUACUAAGUUUCAGGGUUCUCUUCAGCAAUCAUUAAUUAAUACUUCAGCCAUUAAUUCAGAUGCAAAUAAUUUUCUUUUUUCUUUUUUUUGAGAUGGAGUUUCACUCUUGUUGCCCAGGCUGGAGUGCAAUGGCGUGAUCUCAGCUCACCGCAACCUCCGCCUCCCAGGUUCAAGCGAUUCUCCUGCCUCAGCCCCCCUAGUAGCUGGGAUUACAGGCAUGCGCCACCACACCCAGCUAAUUUUGUAUUUUUAGUAGAGACGGGGUUUCUCCGUGUUGGUCAGGCUGGUCUCGAACUCCUGACCUCAGGUGAUCCGCCUGCCUCGGCCUCCCAAAGUGCUGGGAUUACAGGCAUGAGCCACCACACCCAGCCAGAUGCAAAUAAUUUUCUUAGAAAAUUAUUUCAAAAGUUAUUUUAGGCCCAGAAAUCAAGGAUUGUUCCAACCAUGAAAAUGGGUAAGACACCUGCCUUAAGCAAAUCUAACCUGCUAUUACUUGCCAAAUUUUAUAUAUUCUUUUCUCUUGCCUGUAUUUCUAAUUAGUGAUUUGUUUAAUGAAGAACUCUUCAUGUAGAGCAAUUAACUGGGCCUAAGAAAUUUCGAAGCUUUCCAUGACAUAAAGUGGUUAAAAAAAAAUGCUUUGACAGUCUUCUUCUGCCAUUAGUUCAACUGCCUUUACGCUUUUUUUUUUUUUUUUUUUUUUGAGAUGGAGUUUCACUCUUGUUGCCCAGGCUAGAGUGCAAUGGCGUGAUCUUGGCUCACUGCAACCUCUGCCUCCCGGGUUCAAGCAAUUCUCCUGCCUCAGCCUCCUGAGUAGCUGGGAUUUCAGGCAUACGCCACCAUGCCUGGCUAAUUUUGUAUUUUUAGUAGAGACAGGGUUUCUCCAUGUUGGUCAGGCUGGUCUCGAACUCCCGACCUCAGGUGAUCUGCCUGCCUUGGCCUCCCAAAGUGCUGGGAUUACAGGUGUGAGCCACCACCCCCAGCCGCCUCUAUGCUUUUUGUUUCUUUGAUAUAUCUAAACUUAAGGUCAGAACAGAAAUUCAUGUGCUGAACAGAAUGGAUUCUUUUUGCAGUACCAAUCCAAUUGAAUCCUCUUUUUAUUUUCCUGCGUCCUUACCAGUCACUUUGAUAGUGCUAACUAACCUACACUAUGGGGGUUAUUCAUGAAUUAAGUAUGAUAAAAAAAAAAAAGACCUUGAAAAUGUUGUGUACCCUGUGGAUUUGAGGCUUAUUACUACCACCUGGCUGGAUAAAAUGUCAAAACCUUCAAUCACUUAAGGUGACUGGAACUUUUGUAAAAUACACUUAUGAUCCUACUGGGCCUUUUUUUUUUUUUUUUCUGCUUUCCUAAAUAUGAGGCAAUAGAAAUUUAUAAUUUGAGACUACAGUACCCCUUGUUUUAGCUCUUAUCACAGCUGGCAACUGGUAGUGAUUUUUUUUGUUGUUGUUUUGUUUUGUUUUGAGAUGGAGUCUCGCUCUGUUGCCCAGGGUGGAGUGCAGUGGCACGAUCUCGGCUCACUGCAACCUCCACCUCCUGGGUUCAAGUAAUUCUCCUGCCUCAGUCUCCCGAGUAGCUGGGAUUACAGGUGCAUGCCCCCACACCCGGAUAAUUUUUUGUACUUUUAGUAGAGACAGGGUUUCACCAUGUUAGCCAGGAUGGUCUCAAUCUCCUGACCUAAUGAUCCGCCCACCUCGGCCUCCCAAAGUGCUGGGAUUACAGGCGUGAACCACCGCACCUGGCCCUGGUAGUGAUAUUUAAUCCAAUCCAACAACUAUAGGCUGGGUUAAAUAAAAGGUCAUUAUUGUCUAUAUUCCAAGUGGAAUUAAAUGUAGUCACAGAGAUUCCUAACAUUUUCCUUAUAUUUAAGGGAAAUCACUUCUAAAAAAACACACUAAUCAGAACUGUGAUGCUCUAAUUAGAAACAACUCAUCUGGCCAACUAUUUGCUGCUCAGAGUUUCUUAUUUCUUAGAUGAAAAAAACUCAUCAGUUAUAUUCAUGUGAUCGCGGCUAAAAAGUCAGUAUUUUCUUUUUGUUCUAAUGUGGCUUCAUUUGAAAUUUCUCAGAUUCUACAUUGUACUAAUUAUGAAUAACAAAUUAUAAAUUAAAAACUCUUAAAGAGAAAAACUUGGCUUAAAAAAAUCAUUUCAUAUCUCCUUAUAAGCCUUUGUCCUCUAGGUUGUAAUGACUCUGACUUCCCACCUGUGAUGGAAAGCUAAGAGUCACAAGGUCACUAUGUUUACUCUUACGUAAAAGAUAGUACACAUUUUGGCUAGGCUGUUUACUUCAAAAGGCAACCUAUAGGUUUCUACACAAAAAGAGGCACACAUUUGCAUUUGCAUUAGUAUAAUAUGCAUUUGUACGGAUAUUGCUUUAAAAAUUUAUGUAAUCUACUAAUGCUAUUUAUUACUCAUUCCACUGAUCCCUGAAGUCUCUCAACUAGUAGAGAAAAUAACCGUGAUUUAGCAAGAAGCGACAUGGGGAAGGGUGACAACAAUAUACAUUGUUUGAUUAGAUACAGACUCCUUACUGUGUCAGACUCCUGAGGUUCUUUUGGAAUAGUGGGUAGCACCACUUCACCAGAAGAGUCUGAUAUUGCAAUUUGCUGGGUGAUGAAGAUUUUAUCUUGAAGCUUACUUUCAUCCCUGCAAUAAUGACAAAAUAACAGAACCGUCAACAACUCUACACACAUGAAACCUGGUUUAGAAUAACAGACUUGUCAUAUUACUUUCAAUUAGCACAUUCAAGAUGCCCACAAGAACCAUCGUGUUGGGCUCAUGUUUAUUACUUAAGCAAGAGAGCUCUUACCCAAAUUCCUUUGUUUCCCCACUGUCAGAAACAACAUAGUCUGGAACUGGAGGCCUAGAACUCUGGUUGUAUUUCCUGUAGUGGGUAAAAGUCAACAAAGAUAAUGAAUGAGGCAGUGUCUCCUCAUGCCUUCA